GCAGCCGCAGCCGCAGCGACGGCAGCCACGGGAGCCGCCGCGCAUUAUGCAAAGCGGCGGCAGAUGCGAGCGGGGCCAGCCGGGCGCGCGUCGGCCUCCCCUCCCAGCGGCUCCCCCCGCCGCCGCCUGACUCUCCCGGGAGACUCCCUAGGCCCGGACCUGGGGCCGAGGAGGGCCGGGAUGGCCUGAGUGCCCGCGGCGCGGCGGCGCAGCAGCGGGAUUGCACCAUGGGGAACCAGGAUGGGAAGCUGAAGAGGAGCGCAGGUGAUGCUUUGCACGAAGGCGGCGGUGGCGCCGAGGAUGCGCUGGGGCCCAGGGAUGUGGAAGCCACAAAGAAGGGGAGCGGGGGCAAGAAGGCGCUAGGCAAGCACGGCAAGGGGGGAGGGGGCGGCGGCGGCGGCGGGGAGUCGGGCAAGAAGAAGAGCAAGUCCGACUCCAGAGCCUCGGUGUUUUCCAACCUGCGGAUCAGGAAGAAUCUGUCCAAGGGGAAAGGCGCCGGCGGCUCCCGCGAAGAUGUACUGGAUUCCCAGGCCCUGCAGACCGGGGAGCUGGACAGCGCUCACUCCCUGCUCACCAAGACUCCAGACCUCAGCCUCUCGGCGGACGAGGCCGGCCUGUCGGAUACCGAGUGUGCGGACCCUUUUGAGGUGACCGGUCCAGGGGGUCCUGGGCCUGCCGAGGCUAGGGUCGGGGGCCGGCCGAUCGCCGAGGAUGUGGAAACUGCAGCAGGGGCGCAGGAUGGACAAAGGACCAGCUCGGGCUCGGACACGGACAUCUAUAGCUUCCAUUCGGCUACGGAGCAAGAGGAUUUGCUUUCAGACAUCCAGCAGGCGAUCCGCCUGCAGCAGCAGCAGCAGCAGCAGCUCCAGCUCCAGCUCCAGCAACAGCAGCAGCAGCAGCAGCUCCAGGGCGCCGAGGAGCCUGCAGCGCCCCCCACUGCCGUCUCCCCUCAGCCCGGGGCCUUCCUGGGCCUGGACCGGUUCCUGCUGGGGCCGAGCGGCGGGGCUGGGGAGGCCCCGGGCAGUCCGGACACCGAGCAGGCGCUGUCCGCGCUCUCCGACCUGCCCGAGAGCCUGGCCGCCGAGCCCCGGGAGCCCCAGCAACCGCCGUCCCCCGGCGGCCUCCCGGUCUCCGAGGCGCCCAGUCUCCCGGCAGCGCAACCCGCGGCCAAAGACUCGCCCUCCUCCACGGCUUUCCCAUUUCCCGAGGCCGGGCCGGGGGAGGAAGCGGCCGGAGCCCCCGUGCGAGGGGCUGGGGACACGGAUGAGGAGGGUGAGGAGGAUGCUUUUGAGGAUGCGCCCCGGGGCUCUCCGGGGGAGGAGUGGGCCCCGGAGGUGGGAGAGGACGCCCCGCAGAGGCUGGGGGAAGAGCCGGAGGAGGAGGCGCAAGGACCUGACGCCCCCGCGGCCGCUUCCCUGCCCGGCAGCCCCGCGCCUAGCCAGCGCUGUUUCAAGCCCUACCCGCUCAUCACCCCCUGCUACAUCAAGACCACCACCCGGCAGCUCAGCUCGCCCAAUCACUCCCCGUCUCAGUCCCCUAAUCAGAGCCCCAGGAUCAAGAGGCGGCCGGAACCCUCCCUGAGCCGAGGGUCCAGAACUGCCCUGGCCUCCGUAGCCGCCCCGGCCAAGAAGCACCGGGCCGACGGCGGCCUUGCGGCCGGCCUGAGCCGCUCGGCUGACUGGACGGAGGAGCUAGGCGCCCGCACGCCCCGGGUGGGAGGCUCCGCGCACCUGCUGGAGCGCGGGGUGGCGAGUGACAGCGGCGGUGGGGUGUCCCCAGCACUGGCCGCCAAGGCGUCUGGGGCCCCCGCGGCUGCGGAUGGCUUCCAGAACGUGUUCACAGGGCGAACGCUGUUGGAGAAGCUGUUCAGCCAGCAGGAGAACGGGCCUCCAGAAGAAGCAGAGAAGUUUUGCUCCCGGAUCAUUGCCAUGGGUCUUCUCCUUCCUUUUAGUGAUUGCUUCAGGGAACCGUGUAAUCAGAAUGCCCAGACGAAUGCAGCUUCGUUUGAUCAAGAUCAACUUUAUACCUGGGCUGCAGUUAGUCAACCCACACACUCAUUGGACUAUUCAGAAGGGCAGUUUCCUAGGCGAGUUCCAUCCAUGGGGCCACCAUCCAAACCUCCCGAUGAGGAACACAGGCUCGAGGAUGCUGAAACAGAGGAUGAUGGAGAAUCUCAAUCUGCUGUUUCAGAAACUCCCCAAAAACGCUCAGAUGCUGUCCAGAAGGAAGUUGUUGACAUGAAGUCUGAGGGACAGGCCACUGUAAUUCAGCAGCUGGAACAGACUAUUGAGGAUCUGAGAACCAAAAUAGCUGAACUAGAGAGGCAGUAUCCUGCCCUGGACACAGAGGUGGCCAGUGGUCAUCAAGGGCUUGAGAAUGGAGUGACAGCCUCAGGCGAUGUCUGUCUCGAAGCUCUCAGGUUAGAAGAAAAGGAAGUACGGCAUCAUAGGAUUUUAGAGGCGAAAUCGAUACAGACUUCCCCCACGGAAGAGGGCGGGGUGCUGACACUGCCUCCUGUGGAUGGGCUGCCAGGGCGUCCUCCAUGCCCCCCUGGGGCUGAAAGUGGACCUCAGACAAAGUUCUGUUCAGAGAUUUCUUUGAUUGUGUCUCCAAGGCGAAUAUCAGUCCAGCUCGACAGCCAUCAGCCCACACAGAGCAUCUCACAGCCUCCACCACCUCCAUCCCUUCUGUGGUCUGCUGGGCAAGGACAGCCUGGGUCACAGCCGCCCCAUUCUAUUUCUACCGAGUUUCAAACCAGCCACGAACACUCUGUUUCCUCUGCCUUUAAAAACAGCUGUAACAUCCCAUCUCCACCACCUCUGCCUUGCACAGAGUCCUCCAGCUCCAUGCCUGGCCUGGGCAUGGUGCCUCCCCCACCUCCCCCUCUCCCUGGCAUGACAGUGCCUACUCUGCCCAGUACAGCCAUUCCCCAACCUCCUCCUCUGCAGGGUACAGAAAUGCUGCCACCCCCUCCCCCUCCUCUUCCCGGAGCGGGCAUACCUCCUCCGCCGCCUCUACCCGGAGCAGGCAUACUCCCUCUGCCCCCUCUACCCGGAGCGGGAAUACCUCCUCCGCCCCCUCUACCCGGAGCGGCAAUACCCCCUCCGCCCCCUCUUCCCGGGGCAGGCAUACCCCUUCCUCCCCCUCUUCCCGGAGCAGGAAUACCUCCUCCACCCCCUCUACCCGGAGCGGGCAUACCCCCUCCUCCCCCACUUCCCGGAGCGGGCAUACCCCCUCCGCCCCCACUUCCCGGAGCGGGCAUACCCCCUCCUCCCCCUCUUCCCGGAGCGGGCAUACCUCCUCCACCCCCUCUACCCGGAGCGGGCAUACCCCCUCCGCCCCCACUUCCCGGAGCGGGCAUACCCCCUCCGCCCCCACUUCCCGGAGCGGGCAUACCCCCUCCUCCCCCUCUUCCCGGAGCGGGCAUACCUCCUCCACCCCCUCUACCCGGAGCGGGCAUACCCCCUCCGCCCCCACUUCCCGGAGCGGGCAUACCCCCACCUCCCCCUCUACCCGGAGCGGGCAUACCCCCUCCGCCCCCUCUACCCGGAGUGGGCAUACCUCCUCCGCCCCCUCUACCCGGAGCGGGCAUACCCCCUCCUCCCCCUCUACCCGGAGCGGGCAUACCCCCUCCUCCCCCUCUUCCCGGAGCGGGCAUACCUCCUCCACCCCCUCUACCCAGAGUGGGCAUACCCCCUCCGCCCCCACUUCCCGGAGCGGGCAUACCCCCACCUCCCCCUCUACCCGGAGCGGGCAUACCCCCUCCGCCCCCUCUACCUGGAGUGGGAAUACCUCCUCCGCCCCCUCUACCUGGAGUGGGAAUACCUCCUCCGCCCCCUCUACCUGGUGCUGGGAUUCCCCCACCUCCUCCCUUGCCAGGUAUGGGGAUUCCACCUGCUCCAGCUCCCCCACUCCCUCCACCUGGGACAGGAAUCCCACCGCCCCCUCUGCUUCCUGUAUCAGGCCCUCCACUCCUCCCACAAGUUGGGAGUAGCACUUUACCAACCCCACAGGUGUGUGGAUUUCUUCCUCCUCCAUUGCCAAGUGGCUUGUUUGGAUUAGGGAUGAAUCAGGACAAAGGGAGUAGGAAGCAGCCCAUAGAGCCUUGUCGACCAAUGAAGCCUCUUUACUGGACCAGGAUUCAACUACAUAGUAAAAGAGACUCCAGUACUUCACUUAUUUGGGAAAAAAUUGAAGAGCCAUCCAUAGAUUGUCAUGAAUUUGAGGAAUUAUUUUCUAAAACUGCUGUAAAGGAGAGAAAGAAACCUAUCUCUGAUACUAUCUCAAAGACGAAGGCUAAACAAGUUGUCAAGUUAUUAAGCAACAAAAGAUCACAAGCAGUUGGAAUACUAAUGUCUAGCCUUCAUUUAGAUAUGAAAGACAUACAACAUGCUGUUGUGAACUUGGAUAAUUCUGUGGUUGACCUGGAGACCCUUCAAGCUCUCUAUGAGAAUAGAGCACAGUCAGACGAACUCGAAAAAAUAGAAAAGCAUGGCCGAUCUUCCAAAGACAAGGAAAAUGCCAAGUCUCUGGACAAACCUGAACAGUUCCUUUAUGAACUGUCACUAAUCCCCAACUUUUCAGAGCGAGUCUUUUGCAUCCUGUUCCAGUCCACAUUUUCAGAAAGCAUUUGCUCAAUUCGUCGCAAACUGGAAUUACUACAGAAAUUGUGUGAGACAUUAAAAAAUGGCCCAGGGGUUAUGCAGGUUCUAGGUUUGGUUCUUGCCUUUGGCAACUACAUGAAUGGAGGAAAUAAGACUCGAGGACAGGCAGAUGGCUUUGGAUUAGACAUUCUUCCAAAACUGAAAGAUGUCAAGAGCAGUGACAAUAGCAGAAGCCUUUUGUCAUAUAUUGUUUCGUAUUAUCUCCGAAAUUUUGAUGAGGAUGCUGGAAAAGAACAGUGCCUCUUUCCACUGCCAGAACCCCAGGACCUUUUUCAGGCCUCACAGAUGAAGUUUGAAGAUUUUCAAAAAGAUCUCAGAAAACUGAAGAAAGACUUGAAAGCCUGUGAAGUUGAAGCAGGGAAAGUAUACCAGGUCUCCUCAAAAGAGCAUAUGCAGCCUUUCAAGGAAAACAUGGAACAAUUUAUUAUUCAAGCCAAAAUUGACCAAGAGGCAGAGGAAAAUUCACUGACAGAGACUCAUAAAUGCUUUUUGGAGACCACGGCAUAUUUCUUCAUGAAACCAAAACUUGGAGAGAAGGAGGUGUCCCCAAAUGCUUUCUUCAGUAUCUGGCAUGAAUUCAGCUCUGACUUUAAAGACUUCUGGAAGAAAGAGAACAAACUUCUUCUACAAGAGAGAGUAAAAGAAGCCGAAGAGGUGUGUAGACAGAAGAAAGGAAAAUCACUUUAUAAAAUAAAACCAAGACAUGACUCUGGAAUUAAAGCAAAGAUAAGCAUGAAAACUUGAACAAUGAAAAGCAGAAUGAAAAUGAGUCAUUGCAACGACUUUCACAAAAUUCAGCUGACCUGAGAGUGGGAGGGAAACUACCGUCAUUCUGCUCAUGUUUCUUCUUGACCUCUUGCAUAAUCUUUUUGUUUUCUAGACAGUUCACUAAUUGUUGAAUUUUACUGUAUAUUCAUAUAAAAAUGCAAACGUACUAGACCAGUGGAGAAUUUGACACCUUUUCUUUUUGUAAAAGUUUAUGGUAUUAUACCGAUAGACCAAAACAGCAUGUGUAAGAGGCAGUAUCUGCACUAAUUCUCAACAUGCUAAACAUUAACUACAAUUCACUGUUGUGAGAAUAUUCCUCGUCACAGCAAAAACACUUUCCUUUCUACUGACAACCAGUCCUCCACAUCACAGCAUUUAGACAUAUGGGUAAAAUGUUAUUUCUAGUGAAUUGUUUGUAUCAGUUUCAUGUCUAAGUAUAAAUUUUCUAUUUUAAAAUUUAAGAACCGUUUAUAAUCAGUGCUUUCCCAACUCUUGGGUUGCUCUCCAUAACUAUGUAUUUGUGAAAGAAAAUGGUCAUUUUUUUUACUGAAGUCAUAUAAUGACUUGGGUCAGCUCGUAAUGCAUUGUGAUGGUUUUGUAUGAGCUGGGUGUUUUUUUCCAUUACUUUUAAUGAUCUUCGUUGCAAGUUAUAGUUGUGGAUAAAGGGGAGAAUUUAUUGCUCUUGCAAACCAAUUAUGGAAAGCAACUUAAGAAAACCAAUGUUCUAAAUCAUAAUUGUUUGUAUUUAUGUAAAGUAUGGUCUCUUACUUUUUAGUUUGUAGUUUAAGUGCAAAGAAACAGUAGUGGUUUUUUUUCUAUUGUUUUGUAGUCUUCCUGUCCCCUUCAGUCCCUCCAGUGUGUAUAUUACCAUUCUCCAAUGAAAUAAUAGGGCAUUUAACAAAGAUCGCUAUGUGCAAUACUGUAUUUAGUGUUUCUAUUUCAAUUUUUCUAGGAUGUUAAUUUAUAUGAAAAUAAAAUGAAUAAUAAAAGAAUAAAGAUACUUGCAAAA